AUGGGCACUAUGGGGACACUCAGGCCCCAGCAGGAGUCAGAAGGUAGAGAUGGCGGGAGGCCCCCCACUUCCGUGAGGUGCCUGGCCCCUGCCCCCUUCCUGGCUCUGUCUACACCCAGGCAUCUCAUCUCUCCCACACCGGGGGCUCCUGGCUCUGGAAGCCAAUUCCUCCCUUAUCAGCAGCGGCAGCCUUUGGGUGCCACGUCGGGGUCUUGGCCCCUCUCUGUCUGCCCGCGUCUGUCUCCUCUCUCCUCCCGUCAACUUGGGGCUCUCGCCACCCAGUGCCCGCCCCCCCCACCCCAUGCUCCCGUUCACGCUCUCUUUCUCUCCAGCCUCCUUCCAGCGCCAAUCCUGGUUGCCAUGGAAACACUGCAGCGGGUACCAGGUGGUGGCUGGGGGCAGGGAGCCUGCGCUGCCGCAGCCUGCGCCAUUUCCGAUGCCAGGCACCCUCAAGGCACAGAGGCUGGGGCUCAUGUUGGGGGCACUUGGCCUCUCCAGGCCUCGAAGGCUUCUCCUGGGCUGACGCGAGCUGGGGAACGGGAGGGACGGACGUGGGAGCGAGAACGUCACACUGGAGGCAGCUGGUGGCACGAUGGGGGACAGAGUGAAAGGCGCCCUGAUCUGGUUGUGGAAGUGGCCCAUCCCAAAAUAAUCCAUGAAUCUGGGGCACAAAUCCUGCGCCAUGCCAAUCUCCUGGUGGGGUCCCCCUCAGCUCUAAGUGACCAGACCACAGAGCGGCAGCUCUUGGAGGCCUCACAGCACUGGGACCACGCCGUGUUUGUGGCCCGAGGGGCCCUGUGGGGCGCUGAGGACAUCAGGAGAUUGGAUGCAGCUGGGGGCCUCCGGAGCCUUCGUGUCACCAUGGCCACACACCCCGAUGGCUUCCGGCUUGAGGGACCCCUGGCUGCAGCCCACAGCCCUGGGCCUUGCACUGUGCUCUACGAAGGCCCUGUCCGUGGGCUCUGCCCCUUUGCCCCGCGAAAUUCCAACACCAUGGCGGCGGCUGCCCUGGCUGCCCCCAGCCUGGGCUUCGAUGGGGUGAUUGGGGUGCUCGUGGCUGAUACCAGCCUCACGGACAUGCACGUGGUGGAUGUAGAGCUGAGCGGACCCCGGGGCCCCACGGGCCGAAGCUUUGCUGUGCACACCCGCAGAGAGAACCCUGCCGAGCCAGGCGCGGUCACCGGCUCCGCCACCGUCACGGCCUUCUGGCAGAGCCUCCUGGCCUGCUGCCAGCUCCCCUCCAGGCCGGGGAUCCAUCUCUGCUGAGAAGCCUCCUCCCUCCCGAGACAAGAUCAUCUGCCUGGCCUCUCACCACCACCAUCCCACCCCUGCCCUGCCCCACUUCCCCAGGGUCUCCCUUCUGACUCAGUAAAGAUCACCGCUGCCUCCCCCC